GGCUGCAGGGCUCCGGCAACCGCUCCGGCAACGCCAACCGCUCCGCUGCGCGCAGGCUGGGCUGCAGGCUCUCGGCUGCAGCGCUGGGUGAGUGCUGGGGACCCGGGGCCACCGCAGCGUAAGUGACCUUGGCGGGGACGGUGCUACCCGGCCGCCGAGACGGGUUCCUCUGCGCCCUCAGUCGGGCCCAGGCGCGGCCCCGCGGCGUCCCUGGGGGCCGGCGGGGAGCCGGGACCCUCGGGACUGUCCCUGACGGGCGGGCUGGGGUGGGAGUCCGCGCGCUCCGAAGCGUCGGCGAGAAAAGCAGAAAACAGCUCCGCCCGCCAGCCCUCUGCCCUCCGCUCCCCUCCCCGGGCUGUGCGCCGGACCCCGGCCCUCGGAGCGGGGACGCGGCCAGGACCGCCGAGGGAGGCGCCUGCGAGGAAGAGCUCGGCCGGGUCCGGAGACUGCUGCCUGGGACCGCGCUCCCAGCGCCUGGGCCUCGGUGUCUCCGGGCCAAACUGCCGACAUAAUCGCAUCUGCCGGCAUCUAUUUUCGGUUUAUUUCCCCCUCAUUGCGAAGGAUUUGCCUGGCCAACUUUCUGCGCAAGAUCCCACGCAAUUCCUGGGACCCCAGAAGACAGGUCCUGUUGAAGAACAGGAAUCUGGCACUGGGUGGGCUGGGGAGGAAGCCGCACGGUGUUAAAUCCAUAAACAGGAAGAGAAACCAGACAGCGAAACCAAGAGGCGAAUGGGCGAUUGGAUGCCGGUGGGGAGAAGGCCGGGGGCGCACCCUGCUCCUGGACUCCAGUAAAGGGAGGCCGGGCAGAGUCCCUGGGGCGCCACCUCCCCCUCGGUGGAUCUAGGAUCCGGCUUCCAACAUGUGGCAGCUCUGGGCCUCCCUCUGCUGCCUGCUGGUGUUGGCCAAUGCCCGGAGCAGGCCCUCUUUCCAUCCCCUGUCGGAUGAGCUGGUCAACUAUGUCAACAAACGGAAUACCACGUGGCAGGCCGGGCACAACUUCUACAACGUGGACAUGAGCUACUUGAAGAGGCUAUGUGGUACCUUCCUGGGUGGGCCCAAGCCACCCCAGAGAGUUAUGUUUACCGAGGACCUGAAGCUGCCUGCAAGCUUCGAUGCACGGGAACAAUGGCCACAGUGUCCCACCAUCAAAGAGAUCAGAGACCAGGGCUCCUGUGGCUCCUGCUGGGCCUUCGGGGCUGUGGAAGCCAUCUCUGACCGGAUCUGCAUCCACACCAAUGCGCACGUCAGCGUGGAGGUGUCGGCGGAGGACCUGCUCACAUGCUGUGGCAGCAUGUGUGGGGACGGCUGUAAUGGUGGCUAUCCUGCUGAAGCUUGGAACUUCUGGACAAGAAAAGGCCUGGUUUCUGGUGGCCUCUAUGAAUCCCAUGUAGGGUGCAGACCGUACUCCAUCCCUCCCUGUGAGCACCACGUCAACGGCUCCCGGCCCCCAUGCACGGGGGAGGGAGAUACCCCCAAGUGUAGCAAGAUCUGUGAGCCUGGCUACAGCCCGACCUACAAACAGGACAAGCACUACGGAUACAAUUCCUACAGCGUCUCCAAUAGCGAGAAGGACAUCAUGGCCGAGAUCUACAAAAACGGCCCCGUGGAGGGAGCUUUCUCUGUGUAUUCGGACUUCCUGCUCUACAAGUCAGGAGUGUACCAACACGUCACCGGAGAGAUGAUGGGUGGCCAUGCCAUCCGCAUCCUGGGCUGGGGAGUGGAGAAUGGCACACCCUACUGGCUGGUUGCCAACUCCUGGAACACUGACUGGGGUGACAAUGGCUUCUUUAAAAUACUCAGAGGACAGGAUCACUGUGGAAUCGAAUCAGAAGUGGUGGCUGGAAUUCCACGCACCGAUCAGUACUGGGAAAAGAUCUAAUCUGCCGUGGGCCUGUCGUGCCAGUCCUGGGGGCGAGAUCGGGGUAGAAAUGCAUUUUAUUCUUUAAGUUCACGUAAGAUACAAGUUUCAGACAGGGUCUGAAGGACUGGAUUGGCCAAACAUCAGACCUGUCUUCCAAGGAGACCAAGUCCUGGCUACAUCCCAGCCUGUGGUUACAGUGCAGACAGGCCAUGUGAGCCACCGCUGCCAGCACAGAGCGUCCUUCCCCCUGUAGACUAGUGCCGUAGGGAGUACCUGCUGCCCCAGCUGACUGUGGCCCCCUCCGUGAUCCAUCCAUCUCCAGGGAGCAAGACAGAGACGCAGGAAUGGAAAGCGGAGUUCCUAACAGGAUGAAAGUUCCCCCAUCAGUUCCCCCAGUACCUCCAAGCAAGUAGCUUUCCACAUUUGUCACAGAAAUCAGAGGAGAGACGGUGUUGGGAGCCCUUUGGAGAACGCCAGUCUCCCAGGCCCCCUGCAUCUAUCGAGUUUGCAAUGUCACAACCUCUCUGAUCUUGUGCUCAGCAUGAUUCUUUAAUAGAAGUUUUAUUUUUUCGUGCACUCUGCUAAUCAUGUGGGUGAGCCAGUGGAACAGCGGGAGACCUGUGCUAGUUUUACAGAUUGCCUCCUUAUGACGCGGCUCAAAAGGAAACCAAGUGGUCAGGAGUUGUUUCUGACCCACUGAUCUCUACUACCACAAGGAAAAUAGUUUAGGAGAAACCAGCUUUUACUGUUUUUGAAAAAUUACAGCUUCACCCUGUCAAGUUAACAAGGAAUGCCUGUGCCAAUAAAAGUUUUCUCCAACUUGAAGUCUACUCUGAUGGGAUCUCAGAUCCUUUGUCACUGCCUAUAGACUUGUAGCUGCUGUCUCUCUUUGUCCCUGCAGAGAAUCACGUCCUGGAACUGCAUGUUCUUGCGACUCUUGGGACUUCAUCUUAACUUCUCGCUGCCCCAGCCAUGUUUUCAACCAUGGCAUCCCUCCCCCAAUUAGUUCCCUGUCAUCCUCGUCAACCUUCUCUGUAAGUGCCUGGUAAGCUUGCCCUUGCUUAAGAACUCAAAACAUAGCUGUGCUCUAUUUUUUUGUUGUUGUUGUGACUGACAGAGUGAGAUUCCGUCUCCCAGGCUGGAGUGCAGUGGCGCCUUCUCAGCUCACUGCAACCUGCAGCCUCCUAGAUUCAAGCGAUUCUCCUGCUUCAGCCUUCCGAGUAGCUGGGAUGACAGGCACUCACCAAUAUGCCUGGGUAAUUUUUGUAUUUUUAAGUACAUACAGGAUUUCACCAUGUUGGCCAGGCUAGUUUCAAACUCCCGGCCUCAGGUGGUCUGCCUGCCUCAGCCUCCCAAAGUGUUGGGAUUACAGGCGUGAGCCACUGGGCCCUGCCUGUAUUUUUUAUCAGCCACAAAUCCAGCAACAAGCUGAGGAUUCAGCUCAUAAAACAGGCUUGGUGUCUUGGUGAUCUCACAUAACCAAGAUGCUACCCCGUGGGGAACCACAUCCCCCUGGAUGCCCUCCAGCCUUGGUUUGGGCUGGAGUCAGGGCCUGUAUACAGUAUUUUGAAUUUGUAUGCCACUGGUUUGCAUUGCUGGUCAGGAACUCUAGUGCUUUGCAUAGCCCUGGUUUAGAAACAUGUUAUAGCAGUUCUUGGUAUAGAGCAAACUAGAAGAACCAGCAAUCAUUCCACUGUCCUGCCAAGGUACACCUCAGUACUCCCCUUCCCAACUGAAGUGGUAUGAGGCUAGCUCUUUCCAAAAGCAUUCAAGUUUGGCUUCUGAUGUGACUCAGAAUUUAGGAACCAGAUGCUAGAUCAAAUAAGCUCUGAAAAUCUGAGGAACAUUGUAGGAAAGGUUUGUUAAGCAUCUCUUAAGUGCCAUGAUGAGCAUAACAGCCGGCCGUCGUGGCUCACGCCUGUAAUCCCAGCACUUUGGGAGGCCAAGGUGGGAGGAUGACAAGGUCAGGAGUUCAAGACCAGCCUGGCCAACAUGCUGAAACCUCACCUCUACUAAAAAUACAAAAAUUAGCUGGGCAUGGUGGCACAUGCCUGUAAUCCCAGCUACUUGGGAGGCUGAGGCAGGAGAAUCGCUUGAACCCGGGAGGCGGAGGUUGCAGUGAGCCAAGACAGUGCCAGUGCACUCCAGCCUCGGUGACAGCGCAAGGCUCCGUCUCAAUAAUUAAAAAAAAAAAAAAAAAAAAAAAGGCCGGGCGCAGUGGCUCAAGCCUGUAAUCCCAGCACUUUGGGAGGCUGAGGCGGGCAGAUCACCUGAGGUCAGGAGUUUUGAGAUCAGCCUUGGCAACACGGUGAAACCCCAUCUCUACUAAAAAUACAAAAUUAGCCAAGCAUGCUGGCACAUGCCUGUAAUCCCAGCUACUCGGGAGGCUGAGGUACGAGAAUCGCUUGAACCUGGGAGGCAGAGGAUGCAGUGAGCCGAGAUCACGCCAUUGCACUCCAGCCUGGGGGACAAGAGUGAAUCUGUGUCUCACCAAAAAAAAAAAGAAAAAGAAAGAUGCUUAACAAAGGUUACCAUAAGCCACAAAUUCAUAACCACUUAUCCUUCCAGUUUCAAGUAGAAUAUAUUCAUAACCUCAAUAAAGUUCUCCCUGCUCCCAAA